AACCGCGCGGCCCGCGCUGGCGCUGCACUGCGGUGGCUCAGCCCGGAGCCGGCCCGGCGGGGUCGCGGUGGCCAGAGCCGAACGGGGGGCUGCCGCGCGCGGGUGGUGGUUGUCUUUGAGGAAGAGAGGUUCGGGCUCUCCAGACGGCAUCCACGCUUCCAGGGAGGGAGGCGGAAUUUUCUUUUUUCCAGUUCAAACUGGAGAAGGAGGGCAGAGAUAUCCAGUAGACAGAAGAUCUUGGACCCCAGGAAGUAUAUUGGAAGAGGUGCCUGGAGAAAUGGAUGCUAGAAGAAAACACUGGAAGGAGAAUAUGUUUACUCCUUUUUUUAGUGCACAAGAUGUUCUAGAAGAGACUUCUGAGCCUGAAUCUUCUUCUGAACAAACGACUGCAGAUAGCAGCAAGGGAAUGGAAGAAAUUUAUAAUUUGUCCAGUAGAAAGUUUCAGGAAGAAAGUAAAUUUAAGAGGAAAAAAUAUAUUUUCCAACUAAAUGAAAUAGAACAAGAACAAAAUUUAAGAGAGAACAAGAGAAACAUUUCAAAGAAUGAAACAGACACAAAUUCUGCAUCCUAUGAAUCAUCUAAUGUGGAUGUUACAACAGAAGAAAGCUUUAACAGCACAGAAGAUAACUCUACCUGCAGUACAGAUAACUUACCAGCUCUACUAAGACAAGACAUAAGAAAGAAAUUUAUGGAAAGAAUGUCUCCAAAACUUUGCCUGAAUCUUUUGAAUGAAGAACUGGAAGAACUUAAUAUGAAAUACAGAAAAAUAGAAGAGGAAUUUGAAAAUGCUGAAAAAGAACUUUUGCACUACAAAAAAGAAAUAUUCACAAAACCCCUAAAUUUUCAAGAAACAGAGACGGAUGCUUCAAAAAGUGACUAUGAACUUCAAGCUUUAAGAAAUGACCUGUCUGAAAAAGCAACAAAUGUAAAAAACUUAAGUGAACAGCUCCAGCAAGCCAAAGAAGUCAUCCACAAAUUGAACCUAGAGAACAGAAAUUUAAAAGAAGCUGUUAGGAAGUUAAAGCAUCAAACCGAGGUUGGAAAUGUGCUCCUAAAAGAAGAAAUGAAAUCAUAUUAUGAAUUAGAAAUGGCAAAGAUCCGCGGAGAGCUCAGUGUCAUCAAGAAUGAACUGAGAACUGAGAAGACCCUACAAGCAAGAAAUAACAGAGCCUUGGAGUUGCUUAGAAAAUACUAUGCUUCUUCAAUGGUAACAUCAUCAAGUAUCCUUGACCACUUUACUGGGGAUUUUUUUUAAAACUUAAAAAAAUCCUUCCAGUAGGCAAGUCAUUGAGCCAAAUCAGUGUUUAUUGUAUUUUCUUUGCGUAUUACUUAAAAUAUAUGUAAUAGGAUGUUAUUUUCAUUUUCAGUAAAUCACAGUAUCUAUAAAACAUAUACAUGUUUCCAAGCUUCUGCUUUCUCUUUCUGAUGAAGUUAUUGCAGGAAUACAAAUGGAAACGAAGCUUUGGAAAUCUCAUAUCAGAGUGUGUGUGUGUGUGUGUGUGUGUGUGUGUACACACACACAUAUAUUCACUCAAAAACACAUAAUGAUUCACCAAAUCAUUUAUGAAUACAAAUCAGCAAUUUUGUGAUCUCGUAAGCAAAUAUGUCUUUGGCACGUGAAUAUUUUUCCAUCUGUGUUCAUUGAUGUUAACAAUAAAAAUCUUGUUUAUGUGUAUAAGCCUAACAUAUGCCUGUGGGUCUUAUAACUGCCUGUUCAAACUCAAUGGGAUACCAAAAAUGUAUCUGCUUACUUUGGGGGUCUAACUUUAAUUCGGUACAUAUAAACAUCUCUGGAAAAAAAUGUAGUUUUUUUCUUCCCCCUGCUGUUUUCCCCAGGCUUUCUCCUUUGACCUGGCCACGGUUCCCAUAGACUACAAGACGACUUAGAGACAUUGCUGUGACCUUUUGCUAGAGCCCUGCUCUUGCCAGCAGUGGCUUUUGUGUUUUCUUAUGUUGACCAGUAAGGGGCAUUGUUUACACAGUUCUUCCAAAACUCGACCAGGGGAAAAUUUCGAAGCUUCCUCCCCGGCUUACAUCACAAGUUGGCGGGGACUGUGGUGAAGUUGGAUGUCAUCUGGAUAAACUUUUAGUGAGCUGGCUUGAUUUUUACAGUAAUCCAGCCCUGUAAGGGCUCCAGGUGAUGACAAUUUAUUUUACACUUAUACAUGGUAAAAAUGUACUGCCUCAAUCCUUGGGUGGAAGUGAUGGGCCAGUUGACUCUUUACCAUUUGUUUGUAUCAGUCAUCAAGAUAUCCUGUAAUAGGAGCUCUAUUUGCAUGGUGUUUUAAAGCCUAAUAAACCAAAUGUAAUUGCACACUA